AGCAAAGUUCUUUUUACCUUUGCAUGAAUGGCAAAGGAACUAUGAUCCCUAAUGUUUUGGGGUCAGUGUCCUGUGCAGGCCACCCCACCUCUAUAUUAACUCUAUAUUACCAGUCCCCAACCCCACAUAGGGCAGAUGGCACUAGGACCAACAGGAGCUCUGUGGAUACCACAUCAUCCAUCAUUCAGCAAGUGGGCCAACCUCCAACCGUGCCUGUCAAGCAAAGCAGCAGCACUAGCAGCAAGGUUGCCAAAGCCAGCAGCCCAGAACUGAGUUUCAAAGCAAAUAAGAAUGGCCUUCAACCAAGCCCCCUAUUUCUACCUCCAAAUGAGGCUUUCAGGCCCCCAUCAAUUUCCCACCCCAGAAGUUACUUUCCUUACCCAGUACCUAAGGCCACUGCUAUAAGACCCUUCUCCUUACAUGACAAAGGGCCUGUCUACCCUCAUCCAGUUUUGUUGCCCAACAACAGUCUCUUUCUGGGGUGUCUUGCCUCAAAGCCUAGACUGCCUUAUGUGGUGCCCAUGGGCCAUCCAGAGUUUCUGAUCUACCAAGAUGCCCUGGGAUUUGGCAUGGUGCAACCCAUGUUGAUAACACACAGGCCCAUAGAGAUCACCAAAAAGGAGAAACCAGAGAGGAGGUCACAUUCCCAAGAAAGAGCCUGCCGCAAAGACCCAACUCUCCAGAAUCAGUUUUCUGAGAUGCUGGAAGCUAGCAGUACAGCGUUUCAUCCAGAAGUCCCCAAUGACAGUCUAAAACUGAACCCCAGCUGGAAUCAAGGUAAGAUUAUUAUCAGAAGUGAUAAGGUUGUUUAUGUAGACCAUCUCCAAGAAAAAACAGAUGCUAAAACUGAUGCAAAUGUGUCCAAACCCAGCUUCAUAAUGAAAAGUGUUGGCCAGAAUGCUGACCCUGCCAGUCCCCCAAUUGUCAAGCCAUACCUGCAGCAGCAUGGUGAUUUCAUCACCCUAAGAGAGAAGUUGGGGCACAUUGAUGACUUUCAUGAACCUUAUACUAUCAAACAGACUCCAACCAACAAAGAGAAAAAAGAGGUGGAAGCUGGCACCAACAAAGAGAACAUAGGGAUGCCAGUUUCAACAUCAUUCCUGGAGCCAACUCUAGUGAGUGAUGGUCAUGCUGUAACUUUUGGUAAAAUCCAAGAGUAUCCCAAACCAUAUUGCCUUGGCAGUGCCCCACUAAGUAUGGACAUAAUCUCUACUUACACCAAAGAUGGAGCCAAUGAGGCCAAAUCAAGUGAUGGCAAACUUCUGAAACCAAAGCCAUCUAACCUGGUAAAGAGAGUCACCACCUCAGCAGGUUGCAUGGCUGACCGACUCAAGUGUGUUACUACUGAACUGUAUGCAGAUUCUAGUCAGCUCAGUUGGGAGCAACGGGCAUUGCAGGUCACCCCCUCUACCCACCUUUUAGCAACUUUACCUGUAGUUACAGUUUAA